CUCUUCCCCUUCCGUGGGUCAGGGCCGGUCCGGUCCGGAACCUGCAGCCCCUUUCCCAGUGUUCUAGUUCGCCCGUGACCCGGAAUAAUGAGCAAGGAGGGUGUGGUGGGUUGAAAGCCAUCCUACUUUACUCCCGAGUUAGAGCAUGGAUUCAGUUUUAGUCUUAAGGGGGAAGUGAGAUUGGAGAUUUUUAUUUUUAAUUUUGGGCAGAAGCAGGUUGACUCUAGGGAUCUCCAGAGCGAGAGGAUUUAACUUCAUGUUGCUCCCGUGUUUGAAGGAGGACAAUAAAAGUCCCACCGGGCAAAAUUUUCGUAACCUCUGCGGUAGAAAACGUCAGGUAUCUUUUAAAUCGCGAUAGUUUUCGCUGUGUCAGGCUUUCUUCGGUGGAGCUCCGAGGGUAGCUAGGUUCUAGGUUUGAAACAGAUGCAGAAUCCAAAGGCAGCGCAAAAAACAGCCACCGAUUUUGCUAUGUCUCUGAGCUGCGAGAUAAUCAGACAGCUAAAUGGAGUCUGAGCAGCUGUUCCAUAGAGGCUACUAUAGAAACAGCUACAACAGUAUAACAAGUGCAAGUAGUGAUGAGGAACUUUUAGAUGGAGCAGGUGUUAUUAUGGACUUUCAAACAUCUGAAGAUGACAAUUUAUUAGAUGGUGACACUGCAGUUGGAACUCAUUAUACAAUGACAAAUGGAGGCAGCAUUAACAGUUCUACACAUUUACUGGAUCUUUUGGAUGAACCAAUUCCAGGUGUUGGUACAUAUGAUGAUUUCCAUACUAUUGAUUGGGUGCGAGAAAAAUGUAAAGACAGAGAAAGGCAUAGACGGAUCAACAGCAAAAAGAAAGAAUCAGCAUGGGAAAUGACAAAAAGUUUGUAUGAUGCGUGGUCAGGAUGGCUAGUAGUAACACUAACAGGAUUGGCAUCAGGGGCACUGGCCGGAUUAAUAGACAUUGCUGCCGAUUGGAUGACUGACCUAAAGGAGGGCAUUUGCCUUAGUGCGUUGUGGUACAACCACGAACAGUGCUGUUGGGGAUCUAAUGAAACAACAUUUGAAGAGAGGGAUAAAUGUCCACAGUGGAAAACAUGGGCAGAAUUAAUCAUAGGUCAAGCAGAGGGUCCUGGUUCUUAUAUCAUGAACUACAUAAUGUACAUCUUCUGGGCCUUGAGUUUUGCCUUUCUUGCAGUUUCCCUGGUAAAGGUAUUUGCUCCAUAUGCCUGUGGCUCUGGAAUUCCAGAGAUUAAAACUAUUUUAAGUGGAUUCAUCAUCAGAGGUUACUUGGGAAAAUGGACUUUAAUGAUUAAAACCAUCACAUUAGUCCUGGCUGUGGCAUCAGGUUUGAGUUUAGGAAAAGAAGGUCCCCUGGUACAUGUUGCCUGUUGCUGCGGAAAUAUCUUUUCCUACCUCUUUCCAAAGUAUAGCACAAACGAAGCUAAAAAAAGGGAGGUGCUAUCAGCUGCCUCAGCUGCAGGGGUUUCUGUAGCUUUUGGUGCACCAAUUGGAGGAGUUCUUUUUAGCCUGGAAGAGGUUAGCUAUUAUUUUCCUCUCAAAACUUUAUGGAGAUCAUUUUUUGCUGCUUUAGUGGCUGCAUUUGUUUUGAGGUCCAUCAAUCCAUUUGGUAACAGCCGUCUGGUCCUUUUUUAUGUGGAGUAUCAUACACCAUGGUACCUUUUUGAACUGUUUCCUUUUAUUCUUCUAGGGGUAUUUGGAGGGCUUUGGGGAGCCUUUUUCAUUAGGGCAAAUAUUGCCUGGUGUCGUCGACGCAAGUCCACGAAAUUUGGAAAGUAUCCCGUUCUGGAAGUCAUUAUUGUUGCAGCCAUUACUGCUGUGAUAGCCUUCCCUAAUCCAUACACUAGGCUAAACACCAGUGAACUGAUCAAAGAGCUUUUUACAGACUGUGGUCCCCUGGAAUCCUCUUCUCUUUGUGACUACAGAAAUGACAUGAAUGCCAGUAAAAUUGUCGAUGACAUUCCUGAUCGUCCAGCAGGCAUUGGAGUAUAUUCAGCUAUAUGGCAGUUAUGCCUGGCACUCAUAUUUAAAAUCAUAAUGACAGUAUUCACUUUUGGCAUCAAGGUUCCAUCAGGCUUGUUCAUCCCCAGCAUGGCCAUUGGAGCGAUCGCAGGAAGGAUUGUGGGGAUUGCGGUGGAGCAGCUUGCCUACUAUCACCACGACUGGUUUAUCUUUAAGGAGUGGUGUGAGGUCGGGGCUGAUUGCAUUACACCUGGCCUUUAUGCCAUGGUUGGUGCUGCUGCAUGCUUAGGUGGUGUGACAAGAAUGACUGUCUCCCUGGUGGUUAUUGUUUUUGAGCUUACUGGAGGCUUGGAAUAUAUUGUUCCCCUUAUGGCUGCAGUCAUGACCAGUAAAUGGGUUGGAGAUGCCUUUGGCAGGGAAGGCAUUUAUGAAGCACACAUCCGAUUAAAUGGAUACCCUUUCUUGGAUGCAAAAGAAGAAUUCACUCAUACCACCCUGGCUGCUGACGUUAUGAGACCUCGAAGGAAUGAUCCUCCCUUAGCUGUCCUGACACAGGACAAUAUGACAGUGGAUGAUAUAGAAAACAUGAUUAAUGAAACCAGCUACAAUGGAUUUCCUGUCAUAAUGUCAAAAGAAUCUCAGAGAUUAGUGGGAUUUGCCCUCAGAAGAGACCUGACAAUUGCAAUAGAAAGUGCCAGGAAAAAACAAGAAGGUAUCGUUGGCAGUUCUCGGGUGUGUUUUGCACAGCACACCCCAUCUCUUCCAGCAGAAAGUCCUCGGCCAUUGAAGCUUCGAAGCAUUCUUGACAUGAGCCCUUUUACAGUGACAGACCACACCCCAAUGGAGAUCGUGGUGGAUAUUUUCCGAAAGCUGGGACUGAGGCAGUGCCUUGUAACUCACAAUGGGAUUGUCUUGGGGAUCAUCACAAAGAAGAACAUAUUAGAGCAUCUCGAGCAACUAAAGCAGCACGUCGAACCCUUGGCGCCUCCUUGGCAUUAUAACAAAAAAAGAUAUCCUCCGGCAUAUGGCCCAGACGGCAAACCAAGACCCCGCUUCAAUAAUGUUCAACUGAAUCUCACAGAUGAGGAGAGAGAAGAAACGGAAGAGGAAGUUUAUUUGUUGAAUAGCACAACUCUUUAACCUGAGGGAGUCAUCUACUUUUUUUUCCUCCUUUACAAAAAAAGAAAGGAAAUAUAAAAGCCGGGUUUUUGCAACAUGGUUUGCAAAUAAUGCUGGUGGAAUGGAGGAGUUGUUUGGGGAGGGAAAGGAGAGAGAAGGAAAGGAGUGAGGUAUUUCCCGUCUAACAGAAAGCAGCGUAUCAACUCCUAUUGUUCUGCACUGGAUGCAUUCAGCUGAGGAUGUGCCUGAUAGUGCAGGCUUGCGCCUCAACAGAGAUGACAGCAGAGUCCUCGAGCACCUGGCCUGUUGCUCCAACAUUGCAAAGACACAUUAUCAGUCCCUAUUUCUAGAGGGAUUACUUUGAAUUGAGCCAUCUAUAAAACUGCAAGGUCUUGCCCUUUUUUUUAAUCAAAACUGUUCUGUUUAAUUCAUGAAUUGUAUAGUUAAGCAUUACCUUUCUACAUUCCAGAAGAGCCUUUAUUUCUCUCUCUCUCUCUCUCUCUCUCUCUCUCUCUACUGAGCUGUAACAAAGCCUCUUUAAAUCGGUGUAUCCUUUUGAAGCAGUCCUUUCUCAUAUUGAGAUGUACUGUGAUUUUACUGAGGUUUCAUCACAAGAAGGGAGUGUUUCUUGUGCCAUUAACCAUGUAGUUUGUACCAUCACUAAAUGCUUGGAACAGUACACAUGCACCACAACAAAGGCUCAUCAAACAGGUAAAGUCUCGAAGGAAGCGAGAACGAAAUCUCUCAUUGUGUGCCGUGUGGCUCAAAACCGAAAACAAUGAAGCUUGGUUUUAAAGGAUAAAGUUUUCUUUUUUGUUUUCCUCUCAGACUUUAUGGAUAAUGUGACCGGGUCUUAUGCAAAUUUUCUAUUUCUAAAACUACUACUAUGAUAUACAAGUGCUGUUGAGCAUAAUUAAAUAAAAUGCUGCUGCUUUGACAGUAAAGAGAAGGAAGUAUUCUGAUUAGCUGUAUCUGGUAUUAAUUGCAUGUUAAAACACUGGAAUUUUUAAAAUUGAAAUUAGAUCAGUCAUUCUUUUCUUUUCUCAAGAUAUCUCAUGGCUGACACUGAAGAAGAAAUGUAAUUCAUAACUUGCACUAAAUGUAUAUUUUUUUUCUUAAAAAUUUACCAUUCUUAUUUAUAUUUUUAUGGAUUAAAAUUUAUAAAAUACAGAUCAGUUAAUAUUGCACUUAAGUAAUUUUACCUUUUUAAUGUGAUUUUUAUAGAAUAAUUCAGACUUACAAAUACAGAGAUAUGAACAAAGUUUACAGUGGGAACAAAGGUUUAAAAAAAGGUUGUGGUUCUCUCUCUGUGAUCCAGUGUGCACAUAAACCUUUCUCUGAUCUUUCACUGCCAUCCUCUGGAUUAUGUCUUCUGACCUGUCCAUUUUGACCCAUUAACUGGAAAGUUGAAAAACUACAUUAACUGGAAAGUUGAAAAACUACAUUACUUUGGAGAAUAAAACCGAAAGUUCGUGUAUACCUUCUUAAAAAAAAAAUCAAACCAAAAAUGUGAAAACAAUAGAAUUGCAAAGAUAGCAGUUAAAAUUUUAAUCUGAAAAUAACCUUUGAAUCUCGGGCUAGGUUACGUCCAUAUUUGAAGUGGUCAGUGAUGGUUUGAACAUUUUUUGCAGGAUGAGUGAAAAUGCACUGGAUUAUAUUUGGGAUUUUUGUUUUUGGAAUUGUCUGUUUUAAUCACAGCCUUAAUUCACAAUUGGCAAAGGCAGUUUACUCAAAGGACUGGGCUAAAUAUUCUGUAAUUAUGCAUUUUUGAUAGGAAAAUGAAAUUUUUGCAAACAGACAUUUUCUUUUUUUUUGGCUGGAGUGCAGUGGGGCAUGGUCUUGGCUCACUGCAGCGUUGACCACCUGGGCUCAAGUGAUACUCCCGCCUCAGCCACCCAAGUAGCUGGCACUACGGGCACACGCCACCAUGCCCAGCUAAUUUUUUUGUAUUUUUAGUAGAGAUGGGGUUUUGCCAUGCUGCCCAGGCUGGUCUCAACUCCUCAGCUCAAGCAAUCUGCCUGCGUGAGCCUCCCAAAGUGGUGGAAUUACAGGCGUGGGCCACUGCGCCUGGCCCAGACAGACAUUUUCUGAAACACAACUGGCAAUGAGCUGUUUUUACAUUUUGAAAGUGAUUCUUCACUUCCUAGUUCUUAAUUAUAGUAUACCUAUUAAGAUCUGUAAGAUCCUGAAGACAUAAGAUCAUGAAGCCAUAUAAGAAUGAGGAUUGAAAGUUGAGCAAAAUUUUCGGGAUUUUGGGAAACAUUCUUAGCUGUGCUAUCUGCCUAAAAUUAUUCCUUAUUACUUCUCUCCUUUGACAGACUUCAAGUUUUCUUCAUAGCCCUUUCAAAGUUUUUUGAGCCAUCCAGAGUAAAAUCAUUUCUAAAUGAUAGUUCUGUAUAUCUCCAACUCGUCUUAAGUGUAUUUGCCUGUGUGCAACGUAUUGCUAGACUAUGAACUCCUCAGCAUGGCUGCUGGAUAACUUAAUUGUCCUGAGUUAAUAGCCUUCAAAGGACAAAUCGGUUUCUUUGCAGAUAGCUUCGUAAAACUUCACAUGGAGUUUAUUUUAUCAUAUUUCCCUUUUUUAUUUCUGCUCCUCCUUUAAUUGCCCAUCUUGCUUCAGAGACUGACAUUUCAGGGUGGAUAUUAAUUAAAGCAUUAAUUUUGUUUUUUGGUAUAUUUCUAUCCCUAGUAUUUCUAUCUUACUGCUAAAAUACAGGAAAAGUGCCGUAUUUUUAAUGCAUUUAGUGGUUUUCUUUGGUGUUAUCUGUUCCAUUUUUCUUUUUCAUACAUUGAAGUGUGUCUCCUUUUCAACCAAAAUAAUGAAAUAGUGGAGACCAUGAAAUUGUUGUGCCUGGCUAAUUGGCAAAUUAAUUUACCAAUAUAAUAAGUGUAGCGCCUUGUUUGAAUACCCUUUUUGAGAAGGUAUGAUGAGAAUGGGCAAGGGUGUCAGCAUCUCUUCUUCUUAAUAAUUAAUUGUUUUCAGUUUUGGUUCACGAAGAAUGCUUAGUUAAUCUGUAAUGUUGCCUAGAGCUGUAUUUAUCUGUUUUUAUUUAUACUAGUGUAGUAAAGCUGCAUAUCAUUACAGUAAAAACGACUACUGUGAUGAGUUAAUCAGAAAAUCUAUUAAAAUCUAUAUGACAAUGUGUGGUUUGGCCUUUAAUUAUAUCUGUAACAGUCCUCCCUCUUCACUGCUGCCCUACGCAGUGUAGGCCGAUAUGCCUGGCACAGGGAGCCCCAAAAAGGUAAUAAUUAUAAUGCUUCUCUCAGGUUACAAAGCAUUUCUACACUUUGCAAGCAAGGAGCAAUAGAAGAGUAGAUAGAUGCUGGAUUGACAGCAGGAUGUUCAUACCACCAGCAAUGGUUUAGCGCCCCCAUUUGUCAGUGAAAGCUGCAGGUCCACAGAAAACUGAUUUCAUUUCAGCUCACUUUCAAAAGUGAUUUUUUUUUUUUUCGCAAGAAAAAUUACGCUAUUUGCAUGAAAAGAGGUAAAACGAUUUAUUUACAUGUCUUUAAAAAAUCACCUUGGACAUUUGCUAAUAGAACUGCCAAAAGAGGGUGGUAAGUAACAACCUUUGAUUAAGAUGUGGUCUUUUACUAUUAAGCUUUUAGUAAAAAGGAACACACUAAAA